CAAAGCAGCAAUUAAAGUCAGCCCAGCACCAACUCCGACGCCAAGCGUUACACUGGAAACUACUUUUUAAAGCAACAAAAGAGUCUAAAACAAAAUACAACAUUUCUUAAAUACACUGUUUCCAGAAAGAGCUAUUUUAACAGAAGCAACUCAAAGAUAUCCCUUCGACAGAAGUGGAAGUGCUGAAAAAUGCUCAUCUCUCACACAGACUUUUGAUGGACAGGAGGUGCUGCUUUCUGUGAACCACUGAAGUAGAGCAGCUGAAAUCACAAAACCUGGAAGACUUGGCUUUACGUACUCCCAAUUGUGCACUAGAAAACAGCUCAUCUAUUGCUCUAACAGUCUAGUUCUUGAUCUGCUGACCAUGACACAAAACAUUGCUGUUUCUCAACCUAUGAUAAUUUAAAGAGAACAUAAGUUUCUAAGUAUCAUGCCUACCAACAAGCUGUAAAAUGAUCACCCUGAACAAUCAAGAUCAACCUGUCCCUUUUAACAGCUCACAUCCAGAUGAAUACAAAAUUGCAGCCCUUGUCUUCUAUAGCUGUAUCUUCAUAAUUGGAUUAUUUGUUAACAUCACUGCAUUAUGGGUUUUCAGUUGUACCACCAAGAAGAGAACCACGGUAACCAUCUAUAUGAUGAAUGUGGCAUUAGUGGACUUGAUAUUUAUAAUGACUUUACCCUUUCGAAUGUUUUAUUAUGCAAAAGAUGAAUGGCCAUUUGGAGAGUACUUCUGCCAGAUUCUUGGAGCUCUCACAGUGUUUUACCCAAGCAUUGCUUUAUGGCUUCUUGCCUUUAUUAGUGCUGACAGAUACAUGGCCAUUGUACAGCCGAAGUACGCCAAAGAACUUAAAAACACGUGCAAAGCCGUGCUGGCGUGUGUGGGAGUCUGGAUAAUGACCCUGACCACGACCACCCCUCUGCUACUGCUCUAUAAAGACCCAGAUAAAGACUCCACUCCCGCCACCUGCCUCAAGAUUUCUGACAUCAUCUAUCUAAAAGCUGUGAACGUGCUGAACCUCACUCGACUGACAUUUUUUUUCUUGAUUCCUUUGUUCAUCAUGAUUGGGUGCUACUUGGUCAUUAUUCAUAAUCUCCUUCACGGCAGGACGUCUAAGCUGAAACCCAAAGUCAAGGAGAAGUCCAUAAGGAUCAUCAUCACGCUGCUGGUGCAGGUGCUCGUCUGCUUUAUGCCCUUCCACAUCUGUUUCGCUUUCCUGAUGCUGGGAACGGGGGAGAACAGUUACAAUCCCUGGGGAGCCUUUACCACCUUCCUCAUGAACCUCAGCACGUGUCUGGAUGUGAUUCUCUACUACAUCGUUUCAAAACAAUUUCAGGCUCGAGUCAUUAGUGUCAUGCUAUACCGUAAUUACCUUCGAAGCAUGCGCAGAAAAAGUUUCCGAUCUGGUAGUCUACGGUCACUAAGCAAUAUAAACAGUGAAAUGUUAUGAAUAAUAAGGUUCUUUCAUUUCAAUCCCAUCAAAAUUCACUUCACUAACUACUCUGGCGUCAAUGGAUAUUCUGUAUAAUACUAUCAAGUCCCUUUUCUCUUGAAAAAAUAAAUUCAUUAUCUUCAUUUUAAAAACUUA